AAACAGCCGAGAGGACCCGGAAGCGGUGCGCUCCGUCACCAGGGAGUGCGGGAAUCCGCCGUUUGCGCUGAGGCAAUGGCGGCAGCUGCGCCGGUGGCCGCGGACGACGAUGAGCGGCGGCGGCGGCCGGGGGCUGCACUGGAGGACUCCCGGUCCCAGGAAGGGGCAAAUGGUGAGGCCGAGUCAGGUGAGCUCAGCCGGCUUCGGGCUGAGCUGGCAGGCGCCCUGGCAGAAAUGGAAACCAUGAAGGCUGUGGCAGAGGUGAGCGAGAGCACGAAGGCCGAGGCUGUGGCUGCGGUGCAGCGGCAGUGCCAAGAGGAGGUGGCCUCGCUGCAGGCCAUCCUGAAAGACUCCAUCAGCAGCUAUGAAGCCCAGAUCACCGCCCUGAAGCAGGAGCGACAGCAGCAGCAGCAGGACUGUGAGGAGAAGGAGCGGGAGCUGGGCCGCCUGAAGCAGCUGCUGUCCCGGGCCUACCCCCUGGACUCCCUGGAGAAGCAGAUGGAAAAGGCCCACGAGGACUCGGAGAAGCUGCGGGAGAUCGUACUGCCCAUGGAAAAGGAGAUCGAGGAGCUGAAGGCGAAGCUGCUGAGGGCCGAGGAGCUGAUUCAGGAGAUCCAGAGACGUCCCCGGCAUGCCCCUUCCCUGCACGGCUCCACGGAGUUGCUGCCCCUGUCCCGGGAUCCAUCGCCCCCGCUGGAGCCUCUGGAGGAGCUGAGCGGAGAUGGGGGUCCAGCCGCUGAGGCCUUCGCUCACAACUGCGAUGACAGCGCCUCCAUCUCCUCCUUCUCCCUUGGCGGUGGGGUCGGCAGCAGCUCCUCCCUGCCCCAAAGCCGCCAGGGCCUGAGCCCUGAACAGGAAGAGACGGCCUCGCUGGUGUCUACGGGCACCCUGGUUCCCGAGGGCAUCUACCUGCCCCCUCCUGGCUACCAGCUCGUCCCAGACACUCAGUGGGAGCAGCUGCAGACAGAGGGCCGACAGCUGCAGAAGGACCUGGAGAGCGUCAGUCGCGAGCGGGACGAGCUCCAAGAGGGCCUGAGACGGAGCAAUGAGGACUGUGCCAAGCAGAUGCAGGUGCUCCUGGCCCAGGUCCAGAACUCAGAGCAGCUGCUGCGGACCCUGCAAGGGACCGUGAGCCAGGCCCAGGAGCGGGUGCAGCUGCAGAUGGCGGAGCUGGUCACCACCCACAAGUGCCUGCACCAUGAGGUAAAGCGGUUGAAUGAGGAAAACCAAGGGCUCCGGGCCGAGCAGCUGCCAUCCUCAGCCCCCCAGGGCUCGCAGCAGGAGCAGGGCGAGGAGGAAUCACUGCCCAGCUCUGUGCCAGAGCUGCAGCAGCUGCUGUGCUGCACGCGGCAAGAGGCGAGGGCCCGGCUGCAGGCCCAGGAGCACGGGGCCGAGCGCCUGCGGAUCGAGAUCGUGACGCUGCGGGAGGCUCUGGAGGAGGAGACAGUGGCCAGGGCCAGCCUGGAGGGGCAGCUGAGGGUGCAGCGGGAGGAGACAGAGGUGCUGGAGGCCUCCCUGUGCAGCCUGAGGACAGAGAUGGAGCGGGUGCAGCAGGAACAGAGCAAGGCCCAGCUCCCAGACCUCCUCUCAGAACAGAGGGCCAAGGUGCUGCGGCUGCAGGCAGAGCUGGAGACCAGUGAGCAGGUGCAGAGGGAUUUCGUGCGACUGUCCCAGGCCCUGCAGGUGCGCCUAGAGCGGAUCCGCCAGGCUGAGACCCUGGAGCAAGUGCGCAGCAUCAUGGAUGAGGCGCCACUCACGGACGUCAGGGACAUCAAGGACACCUGAGGGGUCAGGAUAUCCCCACCCCCACCCUGGGAAAGACGCCUUUCCCCACUCCUGAACCAUGAGGCCUCGCUCUGGGGUCUUGGAUGGCUUUUCCACCGUCCCUGAGACUGGGGUUGAGGGGACUGACGGGGGCCACCACCGCCCCGCCCUCCAGCGCCUCCUCCCAGGGUGGCUGGGCCUCCUGUUCUCAGGGAUCACACCUGGGUGAGGGGCCCAAGCCCCUCCCGGAACCAAAGGUGCAGGCUCAGGCCUGCGGCUUUCUGGCUGCUGUGCUGCCUCCUGGGCUCCAGCCCUCCCCUGCCCCCAGCCCGUCCCCUGCCCAGGGCACAGCGGAGCCAUGGGGGCUGGGAGUCCCCAUCAGAGGCAGUGAGGUGGGCCCCGGCCCUGGGACAGGCAGCUGCCUUCUGGUCUGCAUGACACUAAGACGCUUGUCCACAGCGGCGACCCAGGCCUCCAAGCUUGCACAGAGGCAAGGCCAGACUUUUCCGUCGUUUAUUUUCAAUAAAUAAGCAGCUCAGCGCA